GCAGAAGUCUGGGCAGCUGCGGGAGGAGAGGUUUGGGAGGCGCGGGAGAUGUCCACCCUGGGCUGGUGGCGCCGCCGGGCGCCGGGCGCCAUGAGGGUGCGCUAGGCGGCUGUUCGUGCCCGAGGCUGCGCAGCACUGAGGUGAGCUUUGCCUUCUUGAUCUUCCGUCCUUCUUGGAGACGACUGGCGAGAGGAAGAGGGACUAGGUCCAAACGCUAGGUGGCUGGGUCCAGAUACCUGUGUUUUGACUCUGUUCCUGUGGAUAGCUGCUUGGUCUGAAGUUCCAGAAAGGAUCCUGUUCCCAGACAGGUCCCUGAGUACUGACGGUCACAGGCUGCCGCGUCUUUCCUGUUGACUCAUGUUUGGUUCCUCCAGUGAAAAUUUUACUUAGAGAAAUGCUGCCUCCAAAGCACUUGUCUGCCACCAAACCUAAGAAGUCCUGGGCCCCAAAUCUGUAUGAGCUAGACAGUGACUUGACUAAGGAGCCGGAUGUCAUCAUAGGAGAAGGUCCAACUGACUCUGAGUUUUUUCAUCAGAGGUUUCGGAACCUAAUCUAUGUGGAAUUUGUUGGGCCUCGGAAGACCCUGAUCAAACUCCGAAACCUCUGCCUCGAUUGGUUGCAGCCGGAGACCCGCACCAAGGAGGAGAUCAUCGAGCUCUUGGUCCUUGAGCAGUACCUGACCAUCAUCCCUGAAAAGCUCAAGCCUUGGGUGCGAGCAAAAAAGCCGGAGAACUGUGAGAAGCUCGUCACUCUGCUGGAGAAUUACAAGGAGAUGUACCAACCAGAAGACGACAACAACAGUGACGUGACCAGCGACGACGACAUGACCCGGAACAGAAGAGAGUCCUCACCACCUCACUCAGUCCAUUCUUUCAGUGGUGACCGGGACUGGGACCGGAGGGGCAGAAGCAGAGACAUGGAGCCACGAGACCGCUGGUCCCACACCAGGAACCCAAGAAGCAGGAUGCCUCCGCGGGAUCUUUCCCUUCCUGUGGUGGCGAAAACAAGCUUUGAAAUGGACAGAGAGGACGACAGGGACUCCAGGGCUUAUGAGUCCCGAUCUCAGGAUGCUGAAUCAUACCAAAAUGUGGUGGACCUCGCUGAGGACAGGAAACCUCACAACACAAUCCAGGACAACAUGGAAAACUACAGGAAGCUGCUCUCCCUCGGAGUGCAGCUUGCUGAAGACGAUGGCCACUCCCACAUGACGCAGGGCCACUCAUCAAGAUCCAAGAGAAGUGCCUACCCAAGCACCAGUCGAGGUCUAAAAACUAUGCCUGAAGCCAAAAAAUCAACCCACCGGCGGGGGAUUUGUGAAGAUGAAUCUUCCCACGGAGUGAUAAUGGAAAAAUUCAUCAAGGAUGUGUCACGCAGUUCCAAAUCGGGAAGAGCAAGGGAGUCAAGCGACCGGUCACAGAGAUUCCCCAGAAUGUCAGAUGAUAACUGGAAGGACAUUUCAUUGAACAAGAGGGAGUCAGUGAUCCAGCAGCGGGUUUAUGAAGGGAAUGCAUUUAGGGGAGGCUUUAGGUUUAAUUCAACCCUUGUUUCCAGAAAGAGAGUUCUUGAAAGAAAGAGGCGCUAUCAUUUUGACACAGAUGGGAAGGGCUCGAUUCACGAUCAAAAAGGCUGUCCCAGGAAGAAGCCCUUUGAAUGUGGUAGUGAGAUGAGAAAAGCCAUGAGCGUGAGCAGCCUGAGCAGCCUCAGCUCCCCCUCCUUUACCGAGUCACAGCCAAUUGAUUUUGGGGCAAUGCCAUAUGUAUGUGAUGAGUGUGGGAGGUCGUUCAGUGUCAUCUCAGAAUUUGUUGAGCACCAGAUCAUGCAUACUAGAGAGAACCUCUAUGAGUAUGGUGAGUCCUUUAUCCACAGUGUGGCUGUCAGUGAAGUUCAGAAAAGUCAGGUUGGAGGGAAACGUUUUGAAUGUAAGGACUGUGGAGAGACCUUCAAUAAGAGUGCCGCCUUGGCUGAACAUCGGAAGAUUCAUGCUAGAGGUUAUCUUGUGGAAUGUAAGAAUCAGGAAUGUGAGGAAGCCUUCAUGCCUAGCCCCACCUUUAGUGAGCUUCAGAAAAUAUAUGGCAAAGACAAAUUCUACGAGUGCAGGGUGUGUAAGGAAACCUUCCUUCAUAGUUCUGCCCUGAUUGAGCACCAGAAAAUCCACUUUGGGGAUGACAAAGAUAAUGAGCGUGAACAUGAACGUGAACGUGAACGUGAGCGCGGGGAAACCUUUAGGCCCAGCCCAGCCCUUAAUGAGUUUCAGAAAAUGUAUGGUAAAGAGAAAAUGUACGAAUGUAAGGUGUGUGGGGAGACUUUCCUUCAUAGCUCAUCCCUGAAAGAACAUCAGAAAAUCCAUACUAGAGGGAACCCAUUUGAAAACAAGGGUAAAGUGUGUGAGGAAACCUUUAUUCCUGGUCAGUCCCUUAAAAGGCGUCAGAAAACUUACAAUAAGGAGAAGCUCUGUGACUUUACAGAUGGCCGGGAUGCCUUCAUGCAAAGCUCAGAGCUCAGUGAGCAUCAGAAAAUUCAUUCUCGAAAGAACCUCUUUGAAGGCAGAGGGUAUGAGAAAUCUGUCAUUCAUAGUGGGCCAUUCACUGAAUCUCAGAAGAGUCAUACUAUAACAAGACCUCUUGAAAGUGAUGAGGACGAAAAGGCGUUCACCAUUAGCUCUAACCCCUAUGAAAACCAGAAGAUUCCCACUAAGGAAAAUGUCUAUGAGGCAAAAUCAUAUGAGAGGUCUGUUAUUCAUAGCUUAGCCUCUGUGGAAGCUCAGAAAAGUCACAGUGUAGCAGGGCCCAGUAAACCAAAAGUAAUGGCAGAGUCUACCAUUCAGAGCUUCGAUGCUAUCAACCAUCAGAGAGUUCGUGCUGGAGGGAACACCUCUGAAGGAAGGGAAUACAGUAGGUCUGUUAUCCAUAGCUUAGUGGCUUCCAAACCUCCAAGAAGUCACAAUGGAAAUGAAUUGGUGGAAUCUAAUGAGAAGGGAGAAUCCUCCAUUUAUAUCUCAGACCUUAAUGAUAAGCGACAGAAGAUUCCUGCCAGAGAGAACCCUUGUGAAGGGGGCAGUAAGAAUCGCAACUAUGAAGACUCUGUCAUACAGAGUGUAUUCCGUGCCAAACCUCAGAAAAGUGUUCCUGGAGAGGGAUCUGGUGAGUUUAAGAAGGAUGGCGAAUUCUCUGUUCCCAGCUCAAAUGUCCGUGAAUACCAGAAGGCUCGUGCUAAAAAGAAAUACAUUGAGCAUAGGAGCAAUGAGACCUCUGUAAUUCACUCUCUGCCUUUUGGUGAACAAACAUUUCGCCCUCGAGGGAUGCUCUAUGAAUGUCAGGAGUGUGGGGAGUGCUUUGCUCAUAGCUCUGACCUCACUGAGCACCAGAAGAUUCAUGAUAGGGAGAAGCCCUCUGGAAGCAGAAACUAUGAAUGGUCUGUCAUUCGCAGCUUGGCCCCUACUGACCCUCAAACAAGUUACGCCCAAGAGCAGUAUGCUAAAGAGCAAGCGCGGAACAAAUGUAAGGACUUCAGACAAUUUUUUGCUACCAGCGAAGACCUCAACACAAACCAGAAAAUCUAUGACCAAGAGAAGUCUCAUGGCGAGGAGUCUCAAGGCGAGAAUACUGAUGGGGAGGAGACCCACAGCGAGGAGACCCAUGGUCAGGAGACAAUUGAAGACCCUGUCAUUCAAGGCUCAGACAUGGAAGACCCUCAGAAGGAUGACCCUGAUGACAAAAUCUAUGAAUGUGAGGACUGUGGCCUGGGCUUUGUGGAUCUCACAGACCUCACAGACCAUCAGAAAGUCCACAGCAGGAAGUGCCUGGUUGACAGUCGGGAGUACACACAUUCUGUAAUUCACACCCAUUCCAUCAGCGAGUAUCAGAGAGAUUACACUGGAGAGCAGCUGUAUGAAUGUCCAAAGUGUGGGGAAUCUUUUAUUCAUAGCUCAUUCCUUUUCGAGCAUCAGAGAAUCCAUGAACAAGACCAGUUGUAUUCCAUGAAGGGGUGUGAUGAUGGUUUUAUUGCCCUCUUGCCCAUGAAGCCACGGAGGAAUCGUGCUGCAGAGAGGAAUCCUGCUCUUGCUGGGUCGGCCAUUCGAUGCCUUUUGUGUGGACAAGGCUUCAUUCAUAGCUCUGCCCUUAAUGAGCAUAUGAGACUUCAUAGGGAAGAUGAUUUACUGGAGCAGAGCCAGAUGGCUGAGGAAGCUAUCAUUCCAGGCUUAGCCCUCACUGAGUUUCAGAGAAGUCAGACCGAAGAGAGACUCUUUGAAUGUGCAGUCUGUGGAGAAUCUUUCGUCAACCCAGCAGAACUUGCAGAUCACGUAACUGUUCAUAAGAAUGAGCCCUAUGAGUACGGGUCCUCCUAUACUCACACCUCAUUUCUUACUGAGCCCCUCAAAGGAGCUAUACCAUUCUAUGAAUGCAAGGAUUGUGGUAAGUCCUUUAUUCAUAGCACAGUCCUCACUAAACAUAAGGAGCUUCAUCUGGAAGAAGAAGAAGAAGAUGAAGCAGCAGCAGCUGCAGCAGCAGCAGCCCAGGAAGUUGAAGCCAAUGUCCAUGUUCCACAAGUAGUUCUGAGGAUUCAGGGCUUAAACGUAGAGGCUGCUGAGCCAGAAGUGGAGGCUGCCGAGCCAGAAGUGGAGGCUGCUGAGCCAGAAGUGGAGGCUGCUGAGCCAAACGGAGAGGCUGAAGGGCCAGAUGGAGAGGCUGCAGAGCCCAUUGGAGAGGCUGGACAGCCAAAUGGAGAGGCCGAGCAGCCAAAUGGGGAUGCUGAUGAGCCAGAUGGUGCAGGUAUUGAAGACCCAGAAGAAAGAGCUGAAGAGCCAGAGGGAAAAGCUGAAGAGCCAGAGGGAGAUGCCGACGAGCCUGACGGUGUGGGAAUUGAAGACCCAGAAGAAGGUGAAGAUCAAGAGAUUCAGGUAGAAGAACCAUACUAUGACUGCCAUGAAUGCACAGAAACCUUCACUUCCAGCACAGCAUUCAGUGAACACCUGAAAACUCAUGCCAGCAUGAUCAUAUUUGAGCCUGCAAAUGCCUUUGGGGAGUGCUCAGGCUACAUCGAACGUGCCAGCACCAGCACAGGUGGUGCCAAUCAAGCUGAUGAGAAGUACUUCAAAUGUGACGUCUGUGGGCAGCUCUUCAAUGACCGCCUGUCCCUCGCCAGACACCAGAAUACCCACACUGGCUGAGGGCAUGGGGUAAAGGUUAGAAAACCUUCACCUAGGACUUGACCCUUACCAAACCACAGAGAAUCCAAACCAAUCCAUGAUAAUGUCAGUAGGAGACUUAACCUUAGUGUGUUACACACCUGACUUAACAUCUCUAAACUCAGAUUGAAAAGAGACCGAAUGUGCAGAUUCCACAGUCUUAAGCUUUCCCCUUCAGAUGUCAGUGUCUGCAUGUGGGAAAGCCAUAGCACACAUCUUACCUUUCCAAGUAAUCAGAUUGAGAAAACCCUAUGAGUAUUCCAGACUACAGAGUUUGCCCAAAUCAACUGUAAAUGACACUUGUGUAACGUAUAUAUAGUGUUUCAUGAGGUGUAUAUAAAAUAGCAAAUUAUGACAGAACAGUGAUCACAUAUAUUUGGAUUUAUAUGAUAUACAGUUACAGUUUACUCUGCAGAGGUACCUUACCUGGUAUUCUUUGAAUUUUUUUUUUUUUUGGAGGAGGAAGAGAGCAACAAAUUUGAUUAUAUUUUUAAGUGUCUUAGAUCCUGAGAAAGAUUUAUUGUGCAUUAUUUGAACCCUGUCAAUAUCUUUUUGAGUAAUUGUUUUGUUUCUUACCCUUAAAUAGUCUUGUGAAGCUGUAGGCAUGAUAGAUAACAUGGCUUUUACUCCUUACUGUUUGAAAAGAUAAGUACUUUAGCUUCUUUCUGCAGCCAUUUCAUCUGCGCCAACACUUUGGAACCUAAUACUGUGUAAGGCUUUACAAUAUACGGAUUGGCUUUUUGUGACCCAGAUUGAUUGGUUGCCACAUGUUAUGUUUGUUGAAGUGGUUCUCAUGCAAAAAUAUUACACAUUUGUGUUCUGGGUUUUUUUUUUUUUUAACCAACUCAAUAUGUGUUUGAUGAUAGUGAAUUGAUAAAACCCGAAGCUUUUCCCUGUAAAUCUUACAUCUUUGCCUUUAAAGAAUGGGUUACAACCAUCACUAGAUCACAGUAGUGCCUAAUGAAGGUUGAGAACCGUAGGAGAGGCUCUCAUGCUGUAAAUAAUGUUGCAGGCUAAUAACCUUUCAUCACUUCCUUUGUGCGCUUCCUGCCUUAAGUGACAAGUAGCAACAUGGCUUGGGUCCCCUGUGCAGCAUCAGCUUAUGCUGCCACAAGUCAGUUUGCACCCUAGGUGCCCAGGAGCUAGUAUCCUUAGAUCUUUCUAUCGCUAACUUAAUUCUCUUCGUUAUUUAUCUGACCCUCUAACUCCAUGUCUAACUUGCAUUAAAAAAAAAAAAAUUCUUUACAGUCAACCCAAGCUUAACAUGGACUCAGGUUCCCCAGCAGCCUUAAUUUGUUUUGUUAACAUCUGUUCCUUCUUUUUCAGCUCUCCUAGAGUAUUUCUGAGUGUUGUGUUCAUCUAAUCUUAGUAUUCUUUUAAUUACAAAUUGACCUCACAGCUUGAGGUUUCUUGUGUCCUAUUCUGUGGACUACCUGUGCUCCUUUGCUUCCCCUCCCCUCGCAUAAUAACUAUAUUAAGAAAUUUUUUUUGGCCUUGAGUUGGCUGGAAAAAAAAUAUAAAAUUUAAAAAAUUUAAAAAAAAAGAUUUGCAAAAUGUAAGUGUAGAUCAUUUGAACAAGCAAAAUUAAAGUACCCACUGGGGGAAAUGUGUCUGAAUCUUACUCUUCUGGAUCUGCAGGAUUAGGGCUUGGAAGUAUGUCAAAGAUGCAGGGAGUGUCAAAGUUUAGGAAGAUUGUAGAGCUGAGAGCAAGAAGCAGAAAUGAGUGAGUCAAAGAAGGGAGUCCUAAUAUAUCACCAGAUCUAGGAGGGGAGAGGAGACAGACAGAAGAAAACACCAGAGGCAAGAACUGUAGAAGGCCAGGUUUCUGAGAAUGAAUUGAGCGGGGUGUCCUGAGCAGUUUGGAAAAGGAGUUUUUGAUGGUAUGGUGUAGGUGAGGGCUGGCUGCAUAGGAAGGACUGAGGUUGGAACGGACAUCGGGAAAGCUGAGGGGCAGUGAGGUUUACUACAUGGGAAAAGGACUCUUGAAACGAGAAUCAGUGUUGAUGUCGGGGUGAACUUUGUGGGUACAUUACUUGGUGUUAACAUUGUUGGCAGUGGUAGCCCCUUUUCAGAAAGCAACUUGCUGUAAGUCAGGGUGUCCGUUCCAACCUUCAGCUAGUGAAAAGGUAGUAACAAAUGGUAAACAAGAGAAUGAUUGUUUAAACCUAUCUGUGGACACUUAAUGCAACUGUUUAAAAAUGAUAAUCACGAGUUAUGUAGCAACGUGGAAAUAUAUUUACAGAACAUUAAGUGGAGAAAGCAGGACACGAAAGUAUAUUUAUACUACAGUUAUAACUCAACAGUUCAUUUAUAUGCUGUUCAUUUAACAGUUCAUUUAAACAGUUCAUUAUAACUGUUUAAAAAUAUAUAUGCUUAUAGUCAAAAGCUGUUGUGGUGUUGUUGUUGUAGGCUUAUAGUUGAGCAUUAUUUUCUUAAAUUUCUUGAAUGUUCUUUAUGGUAGUGUUACUAAAAAGUUUAUGAUCACAUUUUCAUUGUGAACAUAAUUUGAACUCAUUAUCACACACUUGGAAAAUACAGAAAAGUGGAGGAAAAAAAAUCAUAUCCCCACCAUCCAAAGACAUAUACUCUCCUCUUAUCUUGUUCAUUCUUGUUUCUGUGCACAGGUUUAUGAUUAUAACUGUGUCAAAAUGUAUAUUCAAAAUAGCUGUUACAUUACCUUUGUGGAAUUAUGGUUAAAUACUUUCACUUUAAUUUUUUCAAAUGUUCCCUAUAAUAAUGUCCUGAUAACAGUGUAUUAUGUGUGUCUCCAUUGGUGUGCAUAAUACAUACCCAGAGGAAAAAUUAGAAAAUAAAGUAAAUUAUUUUAAAAAAUUACCUAUAUUCCCAACACCUAACAACUACUGCUAACAUCUUGAUCUGUUUCCUCUAUCUUGUUUCAGUGCACACGCUUGUGAUAACAGUGUUAAAUAUGUGUGCAUAAAGUCUUAAAUGAAAAGAUGUGGAAAAUAACUAAAAUAGUGUUGUCAUUGUGGGAAUUUGGUUAAAUAUUUUGUCUCAAAUUCCUUAAAUAAUCUUUGGUGUUUUGGUAAUAAAUUUUAUGUAUGUAUUUUCCAUUACAAAUAUAAUACAUACUCAUACAAAACUUUGGAAAUUCAGUAAAGAAAAUUCACACAUAUUCCCAACACCCAACAACAAUUAACUGUUAACAUCUUGAUCUGUGCACUAGUCUGUGAUUAUUAGGGUGUUAGUGAUAAGUAUGCAUAAAUGUCAAAGAUGGGAAGAAAGAUGAAAAACAAGAAAUAGUUGUGUGGUUGUUGUGGGAUUAUGGUUAUUUUGUUUCGGUUUCCUUGAAAGGUCAUCAUUCUAGUGUUUUGGUAGUCCACCUUUACUACAUAUAUUUCCAUUAUAUAUGAAAUGUGUUCAUUAUAGAAACUUUGAAGUUACAGAAAUGUAGAAGAGAAACUCACCCAUGUUUUCACCAUCCAAAGAGUGUGGUUAACAUCUUGAUAUAUUUUCUUCAUCUUGUUUCUGUGCACAGGUUUUUGGUUUGUUAAUAUGGUUGUGGUCAUUCUAUCUGUAAUAGUGUCAACAAUAAAAAUAAAGUUAAAAAUAAA